AGUAGUUAGGAUGGCUGAAGGGGAUACUCACCGGCUGAAGGCCGACUGUGAUUCCCCCUACCCCCACAAGGCGAUUUUGACCCCCUGAGGGCUGCUCUAGAGGACUCAGGCCCCGAAGCUGUCCCAGGGAGGUCCCCGCUGCAUCCCACCACCCAAGCUGUGCCUCAUGGAGUCGAUGUUUAGCAGCCCUGCCGAGGCGGCGCUGCAGCGAGAGACCGGGGUGCCAGGACUGCUUACUCCUCUUCCGGACCUGGACGGAGUGUACGAGCUGGAGCGAGUCGCUGGAUUUGUCCGCGACCUGGGGUGUGAACGAGUUGCCUUGCAGUUCCCUGACCAGCUAUUGGGAGAUGCUGUGGCUGUGGCUGCACGACUGGAGGAGACGACAGGGUCAAAGAUGUUCAUUCUGGGUGACACAGCCUACGGCAGUGAUGACAGCAACUCGCCUCCAGAAGAGAACCCAUUUCUCUGAUGCUAUCUUCCCUGCAGCUGCUGCGUGGAUGUGCUGGGUGCUGAGCAAGCUGGAGCUCAGGCUCUCAUACAUUUUGGCCCUGCCUGCUUAAGCCCUCCAGCCCGCCCACUGCCCGUUGCCUUCGUGCUUCGUCAACGUUCUGUGGCCUUGGAGCUCUGUGUCAAGGCCUUUGAGGCCCAGAACCCAGACCCCAAAGCGCCUGUGGUGCUGCUGAGUGAGCCGGCCUGUGCCCAUGCCCUGGAGGCUUUGGCUACUCUCCUGCGCCCACGGUACCUGGACCUGCUAGUCUCCAGCCCAGCUUUUCCCCAACCAGUGGGUUCCCUGAGUCCAGAGCCUAUGCCCCUAGAGCGUUUUGGGCGCCGCUUCCCCCUUGCCCCAGGGAGGCGUCUAGAAGAGUAUGGUGCCUUCUAUGUAGGGGGCUCUAAGGCCAGCCCUGACCCAGACCUUGACCCAGACCUGAGUCGGCUGCUCUUGGGGUGGGCACCAGGUCAACCCUUCUCCUCCUGCUGUCCAGAUACAGGGAAGACUCAGGAUGAGGGUGCCCGGGCUGGACGGCUAAGGGCACGAAGACGAUAUCUGGUAGAGAGGGCCAGAGAUGCCCGCGUGGUAGGGCUGCUGGCAGGCACACUGGGUGUAGCCCAACACCGUGAGGCACUGGCCCACUUGCGGAACCUGACUCAGGCUGCUGGCAAGCGUAGCUAUGUGUUGGCCCUGGGGCGGCCCACCCCUGCCAAGCUUGCCAACUUCCCUGAGGUGGAUGUCUUUGUGCUAUUAGCCUGUCCUCUGGGUGCUCUAGCCCCCCAGCUUUCUGGUAGCUUCUUCCAGCCUAUACUGGCACCAUGUGAGCUGGAAGCUGCCUGCAACCCUGCCUGGCCACCUCCAGGCCUGGCUCCCCACCUCACACAUUAUGCGGACUUAUUGCCUGGCUCUCCCUUCCACGUGGCUCUCCCACCACCUGAGUCAGAGCUGUGGGAAACCCCAGACGUGUCACUCAUUACUGGAGAUCUCCGACCCCCACCUGCCUGGAAGUCAUCAAAUGAUCAUGGAAGCUUGGCUCUGACCCCACGGCCCCAGCUGGAGCUGGCUGAGAGCAGUCCUGCAGCCUCAUUCCUUAGUUCCCGGAGCUGGCAAGGGCUGGAGCCCCGCCUGGGUCAGACGCCAGUGACAGAAGCUGUGAGUGGAAGACGAGGGAUUGCCAUCGCCUAUGAGGAUGAGGGAAGCGGCUGAUACCAUGUGGGGCUGGAGACAUAGAUGGACUUAUGAAUGGCUGCUAGGACCUUUAGUGCUCCCUGCACCAACCUCCCAUCCCCCUGCCAAGAUCCUUGAAGGACCCUGGAAGGAGGGAGAGCAGGCAGCCCUUCACAGGAUAGGAUCCGUCUCUGUCCUGUCCUGGCACUGGCACAAGCUCAGCACAUGCCCAGUAAUGCGUGUUGUUUGGCUGAUGGAAUAAAGGGCUUAGGGACUUCCCUGAGGCCUCUGGACCCAUCUGUCUUCCUGAGGGCAGCCCAGGACCUUUGGCCAAUCCCAGUUCCCAGGCUGCAGUUGAGGGUCUGUCCUUGUCAAAAGGCAGGUGCUAGACAGUCUAGACCAGGGUUUCUCAAACUCGUACUUGACAUUUGGGGCCAGAUAAUUCUUUGUUGUGGGGCUGUCUGGUGUAUGGUAGGGUGCUCAGCAGCAUCCCUGGCCUCUGCCCACUAGACAUCAGAAGCACUCCCCCAGUUGUGACAACCAAAAAUAUCUCCAGACCUUGGCAAAUGUUAUCUGUGGGGGAAAAUUGCCCUCAAUUGAGAACCACUGGUCUAGCUAGACCUGCACUGUCCAGUACAGUAGCCACUAAAUACAUGUGGCUAAACUUAAAUUUAAGUUAAUUAAGAUUAAAAGCUCAGUUUCUCAGUCACAUUAGUCAUUCAAGUGUUCAGACAGCCACAUGAGGGGACAGUGCAGCUACAGGAUAUGCCAUCAUGGCAGAAAGUUCUAUUGGUUGGACAGCGUUGGUCUAUACUGACUCUUAUUUCUCAGGGAGAUCACAGCAACCUAAAUAAACCAGAUACCUUUUC